AGUCUUAACCGGGUGUGCGGGGAGCGCAGUCCGGGUGCGUAGGGGCCGCUCGGCGGGGGCCGCGCGGGCAAGAUGGUGUGCGCUCGGGCGGCCCUCGGUCCCGGCGCGCUCUGGGCCGCGGCCUGGGGCGUCCUGCUGCUCACAGCCCCUGCGGGGGCGCAGCGUGGCCGGAAGAAGGUCGUGCACGUGCUGGAGGGUGAGUCGGGCUCGGUAGUGGUACAGACAGCGCCUGGGCAGGUGGUAAGCCACCGUGGUGGCACCAUCGUCUUGCCCUGCCGCUACCACUAUGAGGCAGCCGCCCACGGUCACGACGGCGUCCGGCUCAAGUGGACAAAGGUGGUGGACCCGCUGGCCUUCACCGACGUCUUCGUGGCACUAGGCCCCCAGCACCGGGCAUUCGGCAGCUACCGUGGGCGGGCUGAGCUGCAGGGCGACGGGCCUGGGGAUGCCUCCCUGGUCCUCCGCAACGUCACGCUGCAAGACUACGGGCGCUAUGAGUGCGAAGUCACCAAUGAGCUGGAAGAUGACGCUGGCAUGGUCAAGCUGGACCUGGAAGGCGUGGUCUUUCCCUACCACCCCCGUGGAGGCCGAUACAAGCUGACCUUCGCGGAGGCGCAGCGCGCGUGCGCCGAGCAGGACGGCAUCCUGGCAUCUGCAGAACAGCUGCACGCGGCCUGGCGCGACGGCCUGGACUGGUGCAACGCGGGCUGGUUGCGCGACGGCUCAGUGCAAUACCCCGUGAACCGGCCCCGGGAGCCCUGCGGCGGCCUGGGGGGGACCGGGAGUGCAGGGGGCGGCGGUGAUGCCAACGGGGGCCUGCGCAACUACGGGUAUCGCCAUAACGCCGAGGAACGCUACGACGCCUUCUGCUUCACGUCCAACCUGCCGGGGCGCGUGUUCUUCCUGAAGCCGCUGCGACCUGUACCCUUCUCCGGAGCUGCGCGCGCGUGUGCUGCGCGUGGCGCGGCCGUGGCCAAGGUGGGGCAGCUGUUCGCCGCGUGGAAGCUGCAGCUGCUAGACCGCUGCACCGCGGGUUGGCUGGCCGAUGGCAGUGCGCGCUACCCCAUCGUGAACCCGCGAGCGCGCUGCGGAGGCCGCAGGCCUGGUGUGCGCAGCCUCGGCUUCCCGGACGCCACCCGACGGCUCUUCGGCGUCUACUGCUACCGCGCUCCAGGAGCACCGGACCCGGCACCUGGCGGCUGGGGCUGGGGCUGGGCGGGCGGCGGCGGCUGGGCAGGGGGCGCGCGCGAUCCUGCUGCCUGGACCCCUCUGCACGUCUAGGCUGGGAGUAGGCGGACAGCCAGGGCGCUUGACCACUGGUCUAGAGCCCUGUGGUCCCCUGGAGCCUGGCCACGCCCUUGAAGCCCUGGACACUGGCCACAUUCCCUGUGGUCCCUUACAAACUAACUGUGCCCCUGGGGUCCCUGAAGACUGGCUAGUCCUGGCAGAACAGUACUUUGGAGUUCCCUGGAGCCUGGCCAGCCCUCACCUCUUCUGGAUAGAGGAUUCCCCCAACUCCCCAACUUUCUCCAUGAGGGUCACGCCCCCUGAGGACCUCAGGAGGCCAGCAGAACCCGCAGGCUCCUGAAGACUGGCCACGCCUCCUGAGACCACUUGGAAACAGACCAACUGCCCCCGUGGUCGCCUGGUGGCUGGACCCCCGGGAUUGACUAGAGACCGGCCGUACACCUUCUGCAUCUCACUGGAGACUGAACACUAGUCCCUUGCGGUCACGUGGGACACUGGGCGCCUCCUCCUCCCCCUCCUCCUCACCUGGAGAGACUACAGGAACUUCAGGGUCACUCCCCGUGGUCACAUGGAGGUUGUGGGCCGAGGCGCUUAUUUUCCCUUAUGGUGACCUGAGUCCUGGAGACUCCCAUUCUCCCCCUCUCCCUGAGAGUCCCCUGCAGUUUCUGGGUAACAGGGCACACCCCUCUAGUUUCAUGGGCGAGCACCCCCAUCUGCCACCUCAGACUGACACACAGCCAGCUGGCUCACUUACUGGGGGCCACGUCCCACCCCUCAGAUAUUUCUUUGAAGGGAGAGCAAACCCACCCUGUCCUCUGACGUCCCUUUCCCAACUGUCACCAAACAGACCAUCUUCCCAGGCCUGGGGACCGGUAAGAUCCAUGUCACUAGUUAUGCAGAGCAGUUGCCUUGGGUCCCACUGUCACCAAGGCAACCAGUCCUGCUGCUACCUGUCACCUAGAGUCACACACCCCUUCCCUCAUCAGGCACACCCAUGAAGACAGUGCCUCCCUCCUCCAGCUGUAACCAUGGAUACCACACAUUUCUCAUCUCAUUGGCCCCCACCCCAGAGACCUCCACCUCAACUUCUGGCUGUCCCUACCCUGACUCACCGCCAUGGAGAUCACCCUCCCCGAAGCUGUCGCCAGGGUGACCCAACAUCCAGUUCUCCGGCUCUCACCAUGGAAACAAACUGUCCCUGUCCCCAGGCCCACUCCAGUUCCAGACCACCCUCCAUGCUCCACCCCCAGGCGGUUUGGACCCCACCACUGUUGCCAUGGUGACCAAACUCUGGAGUCCGAGGUAACAGAACACCUGUCCCCCUAGGCUUUUCCUUGUGGACAACGGGGCCCUGUUCACCAAGCUGUUGCCAUAGAGACUGUCAACGUUGUCCUCAUGACAACCAGACUUCCAGUUCUCAGGAACUUCUCAUUGUGGGCCAGAAGUCCUGGGUGCCUCCUACUAGGGCUACCCUACUGCACCCCAUCAGGGGCCUGAUGGCUGCCCCUUCCCCAGACAGGGCUGGACUUCUGGAGCUGCUAAGCCACCCUCCGUUUGCACGUUAACUCUAUGCCGGAUAGCAGCUGUGCACGAGACAAUCUUGCAACACCCGGGCAUGUUUGUCGUCGUCCUACAAAUGAGGAAACCGAGCCUAUGGCGUGCCCUGGUCUGUUGAGAUAUGCAAGCACUGAGCUCCUCUUUUGUCCUCUGAGACCCCAUCUCCAUUCUCACCCAGUUCCUCUCUCCUUCCCUGACCCCCACCCACAUUUCCCUCCUUAGAGAUCCAGGAGGGAUGGAAUGUUCUUUAAAAUUCAACACCCACCAGGCUCUAAGCGGCGAUCUGUGCUAAGAGGUCAGGACCCAGCCGAAGUCCUCGGCGUUGACAGGCAGCUGGGGGGACAUGAUCCAUGGACAAGGCCAUCCCGGCCGUGGGAGACCCCAGUCCCGAAGUCUUGCCUGCAGGAGUACUGGGGUCCCCCUGGGGCCCUCUUUACUGUCACGUCAUCUCUAGGAAACCUAUCUCUGAGUUUUGGGACCAGGUCGGUUUGGGUUUGAAUUCUGCCUCUUCUUGCUCACUGUGUGACCAAGUGACAAACUCCUUCUGAACCUGUGUUCUCCCACUGUACCAGGGCUGUUCUGUGGUCCCCGUGAGUGCCAAGCAUACAGUAGGGGCUCAAUAAAUCCUUGUUUCUUUUGAUGAAUGAGAAAAUGAGGCAGCCAGUGGGUAAUUCCUGUAUAAAUGCACUUUGGUAGAUAAGAUGUUACAAGCUUGGGGGGCUUGGGGUUUUUUUUGUUUUGUUUUUUUGAGAUGGAGUCCUGCCCUGUCGCCCAGGCUGGAGUGCAGUCGUGCAAUCUUGGCUCACUGCAACCUCUGCCUCCCGGGUUCAAGUGAUUCUCCUGCCUCAGCCUCCCGAGUAGCUGGGAUUACAGGUGCCUGCCACCACACCCGGCUAAUUUUUGUAUUUUUAGUAGAGACAGGGUUUCACCAUGUUGGCCAGGCUGGUCUUGAACUCCUGACCUCAGGUGAUCUACCCACCUCGGCCUCCCAAAGUGUUGGGGUUACAGGUGUGAGCCACUGCGCCUGGCCGGGCUUGAUUUUUAUUCUCUUUGGAAGUGGGGUCCUUCAUUCCUCCCCCACCUCCCCAAUCUCUUGCUCCUCUUUCUUCCCCCAUCCUGUGCCCACUGUCUCCCUUUAGCCACCCACCAUGGGUCUGCUCCUUGUCAACUCUGUCCUGACUGGGUCAUUGACAAGAUCCAGGGCAUGAAAUUCGGGAAACUGGAAGGGGGGUUCCUGUACCAGGAAGGGAGAGACAUUACAAACUUUCCCUGACAUGAAUAUGUGGGCUGAGGGCAGGGGCUGAGGAAGCACUGGAAGUUUCUAGGAUACAACAAAGCAUGAAGAGAAAAAAUAGUGUAAGGUCCUGACCGUGCACAGUGGAUCAUGCCUAUAAUCCCAGCACUUUAAGAGACCAAGGUGGGAGGAUUGCUUGAGCCAGAAGGUCGAGGCUGCAGUGAGCCAUGAUUGUACCACUGCACUCCAGCUUGGGCGACGGAGUGAGACCCUGUCUCAAAAAAUAAAAAUAAGUAAAUCUCC